GAAAGCGAGUGUCCCUCUCGCGCCCCAGGCCGGUGUACCCCCGCACUCCGCGCCCCGGCCUAGAAGCUCUCUCUCCCCGCUCCCCGGCCCGGCCCCCGCCCCGCCCCGCCCCAGCCCGCUGGGCCGCCAUGGAGCGCUGGCCUUGGCCGUCGGGCGGCGCCUGGCUGCUCGUGGCUGCCCGCGCGCUGCUGCAGCUGCUGCGCUCAGACCUGCGUCUGGGCCGCCCGCUGCUGGCGGCGCUGGCGCUGCUGGCCGCGCUCGACUGGCUGUGCCAGCGCCUGCUGCCCCCGCCGGCCGCACUCGCCGUGCUGGCCGCCGCCGGCUGGAUCGCGUUGUCCCGCCUGGCGCGCCCGCAGCGCCUGCCGGUGGCCACUCGCGCGGUGCUCAUCACCGGCUGUGACUCUGGUUUUGGCAAGGAGACGGCCAAGAAACUGGACUCCAUGGGCUUCACGGUGCUGGCCACCGUAUUGGAGUUGAACAGCCCCGGUGCCAUCGAGCUGCGUACCUGCUGCUCCCCUCGCCUAAGGCUGCUGCAGAUGGACCUGACCAAACCAGGAGACAUUAGCCGCGUGCUAGAGUUCACCAAGGCCCACACCACCAGCACCGGCCUGUGGGGCCUCGUCAACAACGCAGGCCACAAUGAAGUAGUUGCUGAUGCGGAGCUGUCUCCAGUGGCCACUUUCCGUAGCUGCAUGGAGGUGAAUUUCUUUGGCGCGCUCGAGCUGACCAAGGGCCUCCUGCCCCUGCUGCGCAGCUCAAGGGGCCGCAUCGUGACUGUGGGGAGCCCAGCGGGGGACAUGCCAUAUCCGUGCUUGGGGGCCUAUGGAACCUCCAAAGCGGCCGUGGCGCUACUCAUGGACACAUUCAGCUGUGAACUCCUUCCCUGGGGGGUCAAGGUCAGCAUCAUCCAGCCUGGCUGCUUCAAGACAGAGUCAGUGAGAAACGUGGGUCAGUGGGAAAAGCGCAAGCAAUUGCUGCUGGCCAACCUGCCUCAAGAGCUGCUGCAGGCCUACGGCAAGGACUACAUCGAGCACUUGCAUGGGCAGUUCCUGCACUCGCUACGCCUGGCCAUGUCCGACCUCACCCCAGUUGUAGAUGCCAUCACAGAUGCGCUGCUGGCAGCUCGGCCCCGCCGCCGCUAUUACCCCGGCCAGGGCCUGGGGCUCAUGUACUUCAUCCACUACUACCUGCCUGAAGGCCUGCGGCGCCGCUUCCUGCAGGCCUUCUUCAUCAGUCACUGUCUGCCUCGAGCACUGCAGCCUGGCCAGCCUGGCACUACCCCACCACAGGACGCAGCCCAGGACCCAAACCUGAGCCCCGGCCCUUCCCCAGCAGUGGCUCGGUGAGCCAUGUGCACCUAUGGCCCAGCCACUGCAGCACAGGAGGCUCCGUGAGCCCUUGGUUCCUCCCCGAAAACCCCCAGCAUUACGAUCCCCCAAGUGUCCUGGACCCUGGCCUAAAGAAUCCCACCCCCACUUCAUGCCCACUGCCGAUGCCCAAUCCAGGCCCGGUGAGGCCAAGGUUUCCCAGUGAGCCUCUGCGCCUCUCCACUGUUUCAUGAGCCCAAACACCCUCCUGGCACAACGCUCUACCCUGCAGCUUGGAGAACUCCGCUGGAUGGGGAGUCUCAUGCAAGACUUCACUGCAGCCUUUCACAGGACUCUGCAGAUAGUGCCUCUGCAAACUAAGGAGUGACUAGGUGGGUUGGGGACCCCCUCAGGAUUGUUUCUCGGCACCAGUGCCUCAGUGCUGCAAUUGAGGGCUAAAUCCCAAGUGUCUCUUGACUGGCUCAAGAAUUAGGGCCCCAACUACACACCCCCAAGCCACAGGGAAGCAUGUACUGUACUUCCCAAUUGCCACAUUUUAAAUAAAGACAAAUUUUUAUUUCUUCUAAAA